AUGAAACUCCUGCGGGUCUUUGGCCUGAAAGUUGGGAAUGGUUGGGGGAGAGAAGGGCAGCAGCUUAUUGGUGGUCUUUUCACCAUUGGCAGAAACAGUGUAGUAUCUGGGGCGAGUGUUGGGGGUAAAAGCCCACCCUACAGAAAGUGGAACAGCCCGGAGCCUGAUGUGAAAGGACCACGGGUGUUGAAGCACUGCUUCCUGGACUCCUAUCUGAGAAGGUCCGUGGGCUUCGGGAUUCUGCAGUGGCGGGCAGUUCCCCCACUUGCCAAAGAGUCCAUUCAGGCUCUGCCCGGUGGGACACAGAAAACAGAAGCCAGAGGAGGCUCUCCUAGCGGGCCGUUGGCCUCCUUGGGCCCGCGGAAGGCGGCCCUUUGGGAGCGCCUCUCUGCACCGUCCCAGCUCCGCUCCCCUCUCGGGGAAGUUGUGGGCCUCGGGGCGGAGUCCCUGCGGUGGGGAAGGCGCGGGCUCUCCCAGACCAGGAGGAGGGGGACCCACCCACCUCUCUUCUUCUGCGCUGAUGAGGCCACUCCGCUAGCAAGGGACAGAGCUGCGUAUCUGAGGAGCUGGACCCUAGAGUUGCCCUGGAAACCUCCUCAGCUGCGUGUCCAGCGCUCCCUGAGGCCGGGGAAGACUGGGCCUCUUUUUGGACCCCCAUUGGGUGCCUGGCACAUAGUAGGUGUGCAUCAGAGUUUGCUGAAUGGAAUAGAGGCUGCAGCACCCCGUGCGCCACCCCAGAGCCCUGUGGGUGUGAAGGUAAAGGCCUGGGCCCGUCCCUCGGGGGAAGGACAGGCACCUUGGGUGGGUUGUGGCCAGGCUCUGCACCCUUUUCCAGCCUGGUCUGUUCUUCUGCCUGUGGGACCCCCCAAGUCCCCCAGGGCAGCCCAGCCUCUCCUCUCUUUCAGGGCCUUGGCAACCCAGCCCUCAUCGGCUGCAUGUAUCCUUGGAGAUGAGGCUCUGGGAGCCCAAACACAGGCCGCAGAGCUGUGGGAAGAGCCAUUCUUCCCUCCUCCACCUCUCCCUGCCCCUGGGGAGCUGUGGACCUCCCAGAACCAGGCCUGCUGGAAGGAAUGCAUCCAAAAGGAGGCCACCACCCAAGUUGCCUGGAAGAUCAACGAUGGCCACAAGUACCUAAGGGAGGGGACCGUGCCCAGGAAGCAGCUCCAGCAGGCCCCAUCCAGGUCAGCCUUGGUAGCGGGCCCAGUGCCUGCCACCAGCUCCCGUGAUAGCAAGGAGGUACAGGUUGGAUGGCCAGAGACCAAGGGGGCCCAGAACCAGCUGUCCAAGGGAGUGGGUGUCCAGGACUCCCCACCCAAGGGAGACAGAGUCUGGAAGGCCAGAAAAGCAACUCAGGGGCCAGCAGGUCAGACCAGGCCGGAGAGUUUAGAAAUGAGGCAGGUCUCCCCAAGAAUCCUGCAGCUGCUCUUCCCAGGCAUCUCCCACGAUGGCCAAGGCCACGCCCUGGACCUCCAGGCACGGCAUCGGCUGAAGCCCGAGGAGAAGUUCCAGUACCCAGUCAUGUCAUCCUAGGAGUACAGCUGGCACGUGGGUAAGGGCCACCACCAUCUUGCCAUUCCAGGCCUCUGGCAGGCAGGCCUGGCCUCCCUCCCCAGCCUCAUCCUUCACCACCCCUCACCCCGGCUCAUGGACCUGGAUCACCUUCCUCUGAGCACAUAGACCUUGGGGAUGUGCUUAGGCACCUUCACACUUCCAGGCCUUUUCAUGCUCUGGUCUCUCCACUUGGGAUGCUCCUCCUGCUGCCCCACCCUGAUGAAAUUUCACACAUCACCUCCUCUGGGAAGUCUUCUGAGAUGCCUCCAAGCAGAUUAGUUGAGCCCACCUUCAUGCUUCUGCAGGUUUUUGAGUCCACAGAAGCACUGGGCACACGGAAUCACCAUUCCUUAUAUAUCCAUCUGGCCUGGGGAGCCCUUUGGGUUCCAAGACUUCUUAGUUAACUUUAUUCAUGCCCUCCCAGCUCCCAGCCUGGGGCUGGUACUUGACUGUGGAAUGAAUGAACAAAUGAAUGAACAUGGACUAGGGAUGAGAACUUGAUUUGCAAUCAGGAGGUAUGAGUUCAAAUCCUGGUUCUACCACUUCUGAGUUGUAUGAUCUCAGGCAAGAGCCUCAACUUCUCUGGGCCUCAAUUUUCACAUCUGAAAAAUGGGAAUAACCUAGUAUGUGCCUUCCUGUGUCAUGGAGUUUUGGGGAAAUCAAGUGGGAAAGCACUUGGAAUAGGAACUGUCCUCACAAACCCCCUGUGAGGUAGGAACCAAGUGUGAUUCCAUCAUUCAGAAUGGAGAGGAGAUCUGGAGUUACUGAAUCCCAGCUCUACCUGGAAAUGAGUCACUGAACAAACAAGCACAGAAUUGUGAAUCAGUUUAAUUAGGAGGCUUGGGUUUGAUUUCUGGCUCAUUCAUUCAUUCAGUCUGUCAAUCAUUUAACAAGUGUUUAUUGAGCUCCUGGUAUGUGUCAGACACUUACACUUUUUGUCCCUGGGCAUACAACAGAGAACAAGACAGACAUGAUCCCUGCCCUCACCAAAGGUAGACAACAAACAGAUAAUGAUGCGGUGUCAGGCAGUGGUCCACACUACUACAGAGCAGCCCUUUUCCAUCUUUCCUAUGCACAGGAAUCAGCUGGGGUCUUGGUAAAAUGCAGGUUCUGACUGGGGCAGGGAGUGGGCGGUGAUGGGGGAACUUCUGCAUUUCUAACAAGUUCCCAGAUGGUGCCGAUGCUGCUGGUCCAUGGACCAUACCUCGAGGUCAAGGCUAAAGGAGAAGAUAAGUUAGAAGAAGGAGAUGGCCAGGUAUGAUGGCUCAUGCCUGUAAUCCCAGUGCUUUGGGAGGCCAAGGCAAAAUAAUCACUUGA